CUACCCCCCUUGGGGCGACCGUGGGGAGGUGCCGCCGGGGUCGCAGGUGAGCGGUUCUAUGCUGGAGGAGGCGGCCAGGGAAGCGGCGGCUCCGUGACCAGUGGGUGCCCUCGCAGUGGGUAGGGUCCCGGAGGGGUCAGCGGCAAUUGGCGCAACGCUUGCUGCCGGGUUUGGUCCAAGGGCUGCGACGUAGCGGGACUGCACGCUCGGGAGAAGUGCCACGCGCGUCUGUCGCCUGACCGGGGAGGCUGGGGAGGGCCCAGGCCACGGAAACAAGACUGCAGAAGUUUCUGGGCACUCAGUCGGGACUCUCAUUUAAUACCCAGAGAGAGGAGAUCUUCCAGGUUGCCCCGACUCCCACCGGGACUCCUACCAGCAGCAACCUCAUCAUUGUGGCCGAGGCAGGUGCGCGCCCCUGCUCCCCUGGGUGGCCUUCCGGGAGCCCAGUCUAACUCGAUUCUUCCCAGGGGCUCUUUUUGGACGGUCCCAAAGGAGGCAGCGGGAGGGAGGUGAAAGAUACUUUGAUAACCGUCGACCCAUAAGUAUACUUGUUAUGCACCUACCACGAGUUUUAGAGAAGAACAUACUUUUUGGCAGGGAAGUGAAUCCCCUAUAAGAAUAUAGGGGAGGGGAAAGCCACACUUUAAAGAGAAUUUGGGUAGGGUUUGAUAUUGUAGAUUUGUGAUGCUUUUCUUCUUGAACUGCUUAACUAAUUUACCCUCAAAUUUUUUUGAUCCGGAACUUGCCGUCUGGUUUUUCUCAGACUUCUUAAUUCUGACUUAUCAUGAAGUAUCUAGGAACUUCAUUCUCAAGUUUUAGUGCUUGUAAAAAGUUGCCUGGUUAUAUUAUGCCAUUGGCAGUACAUCAUCUUCACAAGGAUUACGUAAGUGAACUACAUCUCAUUCCUGUUUCCAACUAGUGAAGAACGAUUGUGAAAUGGGAUUUUAGAAAAUGGCUGUUCUCUGUGAUUGGGCAUAGAAGGUUUGUAAGUUUUAGAGACUGCAGCUGUUGAAUCCUUUCUGCUAAGAGAGCGAUGACAGGCAAUAGAAAAGGGAUAGUGUUUGACAUCUAAAAUGACAUAUUUUCACAUUUUAUGAGGUGUUAUAUCCCCAGCACCAAAAAUAGUGCCUUUCACACAGUAGGAGCUCAGUAAGUAUUUUUUGAGGAAAUUAUUGGGGAAUGAAUGGAUGGUAGAAAACCCAAGCUUCUGUUACUUGGAUACCGGCAUAUAAAGGAGAGGACAGGAAGACAAACAUUUCUGGAAAUGGCUUUUAUCCAGGGAUUCUUCAGGCCAGGUCUCCGGUCUAAUUUACUUUAACAGGAGGUAGAGGAAAUGUAACCGAUUGAAAGAAUUUUAUCUGGACCUUCCACAUAGGAAUUAUCCAGACUGCCUUGCCACUAGAUGAAUGGAAGACAAUGAUUUGAACUAAGGGCCAGCAAAGAAUUAUCCCUGGUUUUUGUGCUUUGCAGCAUUCCUCAAAUUGUUUUCACAUCUCUUACCAUAAAAACUGCAUUGAAAUUGAAAAUGAAGCAGUUGAAAAGAAAAAGGAAAAGCAAUUUUAGUGUUCAAGAAACUCAGACCCUUUUGAAAGAAAUUACGAAAAGGAAAGAAGUCAUUUUUUCCAAGCAGCUCAAUACAACAAUUAAUGUGAUGAAGCGAAUGGCUUGGGAAGAGAUUGCACAGUGUGUGAAUGCUGUAGGAGAAGGAGAACAGAGGACAGGGACAGAGGUGAAAAGAAGGUACCUUGACUGGCGAGCACUUAUGAAGAGAAAGAGGAUGAAGGCCAACAUUAAGCUGGUUGGUUCAGGAUUUCCCCUUCCCUCCUCUGAUUUGGAUGACUCUCUCACUGAAGAGAUAGAUGAAAAGAUUGGAUUCCGAAAUGAUGCAAAUUUUGACUGGCAAAAUGUGGCAGAUUUCAGGGAUGCAGGUGGAUCCUUAACUGAGGUCAAGGUGGAAGAGGAAGAAAGGGAUCCGCAGAGUCCUGAAUUUGAAAUUGAGGAGGAGGAAGAAAUGUUGUCAUCCGUCAUACCAGAUUCCAGGAGAGAAAAUGAACUUCCCGAUUUCCCCCACAUUGAUGAGUUUUUUACCCUUAACUCAACACCAUCUAGAUCUGCAUAUGAUGAGCCUCAUUUGCUCGUAAAUAUUGAGAAACAGAAACUAGAGUUGGAAAAACGACGACUGGAUAUCGAGGCCGAAAGGCUGCAGGUAGAAAAGGAACGCCUACAAAUCGAGAAAGAGAGGCUGCGGCAUUUAGACAUGGAACAUGAGCGGCUUCAGCUAGAGAAGGAGCGGCUGCAGAUUGAAAGAGAAAAGUUGAGGUUACAGAUAGUCAAUUCAGAGAAACCGUCCUUGGAAAAUGAACUUGGUCAAGGAGAAAAAUCCAUGCUUCAACCACAGGACAUAGAAACAGAGAAGUUAAAACUUGAGCGAGAACGCUUGCAACUGGAAAAGGAUAGGCUGCAGUUUUUGAAGUUUGAAUCUGAGAAGCUGCAGAUUGAAAAGGAACGCUUACAGGUAGAGAAAGACAGACUUCGAAUUCAGAAAGAAGGACACUUGCAGUGAUUUUUCCAGGCUUCCAUUUAGCAAAUGUUUGAAAACUCUAGAUUUUUCUCAUAUCAGGUGAUAUAAUGAUGGUUGCUGGAUUAGCUGUGGUUUCUUGUCUAAUGUCAGUGUUCAGUAGGAAAAAGUUAUAUGUGGAUAACUGUAUGCCUAAGUAGUAUAUAAAAGCUGUGCCCUAGCGUAAACAGUAUAGCAGAAACUUACUGUGCUGGACUCUUUACCUUAUAAUAUUACAUAGAGUCUUGUAUUGUCUGUGUACCCAGAGUUUACAAUUAUGUCCAUAUAAAAUUCUAGCCCAGAAGUUCUCAUCUGGGGUAGAUUUUGGCCUUCAGAAGACCAAUUUGGUGAUGUCUGGAGACAUGUUGGGUUGUCAAAACUGGGGUGGGGAAAAGGUUGCUACUGUGCAAUGCAUACCUCCUCAACACCCCCCCACACUCAGUAAAGAAUUUUCCAACCCAAAAUAUCAUUAGUCCUGAGGUUGAGAAACCCUGUCCUAGCCUAACUGUGUACCUCUAUAGCUAUGUUUUAUAGUUUUAGAAUAUUAAAACCUCAGAUAUUUAUGUGGGUAGGUACUUAAAUGGCCAAAAACUUUAACUAUGAAAUGUUACUGUGUAGUAUAUUGAAUAUAGGAAGUGAUGAAGAUUAUAGGUAUUUUAUUCCCAUGUUUCCAUCUAUAAAUAGCCUUCUCAGAUUCAGAAAACAAUACAGAGAACAUCAGAAAUUUUCUAAAAUGGGUCACUUUGAAAAGAAUUCUUUUUCUCACUAUUAAUGCUUUAGAAGCAAGACGCAAUUUUAAAGCUUUAGUUCCUUUUCUUUCAGUCAUUGUCUUAGUUUGGGUACAAAAAUGUCAUUUCAGUAAUGUACUGAAAUCUUAUAAGUGAAUAGUUGAAGCUAGUAAAAAUGAUACCAGUAUAAAAAUGGUACUUGUAGUCCAUGAGCUUGAACCCAAUGACUGAUUGUUUGACUUUUAAAAUAAGUAAUAGCAGCCAUUUGGGAGUAGGGGGUAGGUGGGGAAGAUGUACUCCGUAUCAAAUAAUAAUGAUGUUGAAAUAAUGAUAGUAGGUAUGUAUUAUGGAUUGGAGAAGCACUUAUUACACUAUCUAACCUAAUAUGUAGAACAAUUCUUGAGAGUUGUAUCUGUCGUUAUUUCUGAAUGUGAAGCUCAGAGAAGUGACACAGAGUAAAUGGCUGAUCUUCUAUAUUGUAGUAUAUUUUGUCCUUCCCUCUUCCCUGAGGAACAAAGCACGUAUCUUUAGUCUCUUUGAUAUUUAUUCUGAGACCAAGGGCUUGCUUGACCUGAUGAUUUUCCUUCAGCUCUCUGAAGGUGCUUUUUCCACAAUCCAAGUGAUUCUGAUACACACUAAAGUUGAGAAUCACUGCACUAGAUCACUUUGUGUUUUCUGAUUUUCAAGGUUGAUACGUAGCUUUAAUACAGCUCUUCUGUUGACAGUUAUUACUUUAAUUUUGCAUUUGUUCCUUGUAAGAAUGGCUGGAAACUGUGUGUUGACAUUUGAGGAUGGGUAUGCAAGGAAAAAAUAUACUUCUGUUUACUUACUCUGACUUUGAAAUAGUGUUAUUUUUCUAUAUCUGAAAUAAAUGCUUCUACCAUAGAAAUAAAUUUGCCUAUACUAUCUGAGAA